AGGUCAUGCCCGUGUGAGCCAGGAAAGGGCUGUGUUUAUGGGAAGCCAGUAACACUGUGGCCUACUAUCUCUUCCGUGGUGCCAUCUACAUUUUUGGGACUCGGGAAUUAUGAGGUAGAGGUGGAGGCGGAGCCGGAUGUCAGAGGUCCUGAAAUAGUCACCAUGGGGGAAAAUGAUCCGCCUGCUGUUGAAGCCCCCUUCUCAUUCCGAUCGCUUUUUGGCCUUGAUGAUUUGAAAAUAAGUCCUGUUGCACCAGAUGCAGAUGCUGUUGCUGCACAGAUCCUGUCACUGCUGCCAUUGAAGUUUUUUCCAAUCAUCGUCAUUGGGAUCAUUGCAUUGAUAUUAGCACUGGCCAUUGGUCUGGGCAUCCACUUCGACUGCUCAGGGAAGUACAGAUGUCGCUCAUCCUUUAAGUGUAUCGAGCUGAUAGCUCGAUGUGACGGAGUCUCGGAUUGCAAAGACGGGGAGGACGAGUACCGCUGUGUCCGGGUGGGUGGUCAGAAUGCCGUGCUCCAGGUGUUCACAGCUGCUUCGUGGAAGACCAUGUGCUCCGAUGACUGGAAGGGUCACUACGCAAAUGUUGCCUGUGCCCAACUGGGUUUCCCAAGCUAUGUGAGUUCAGAUAACCUCAGAGUGAGCUCGCUGGAGGGGCAGUUCCGGGAGGAGUUUGUGUCCAUCGAUCACCUCUUGCCAGAUGACAAGGUGACUGCAUUACACCACUCAGUAUAUGUGAGGGAGGGAUGUGCCUCUGGCCACGUGGUUACCUUGCAGUGCACAGCCUGUGGUCAUAGAAGGGGCUACAGCUCACGCAUCGUGGGUGGAAACAUGUCCUUGCUCUCGCAGUGGCCCUGGCAGGCCAGCCUUCAGUUCCAGGGCUACCACCUGUGCGGGGGCUCUGUCAUCACGCCCCUGUGGAUCAUCACUGCUGCACACUGUGUUUAUGACUUGUACCUCCCCAAGUCAUGGACCAUCCAGGUGGGUCUAGUUUCCCUGUUGGACAAUCCAGCCCCAUCCCACUUGGUGGAGAAGAUUGUCUACCACAGCAAGUACAAGCCAAAGAGGCUGGGCAAUGACAUCGCCCUUAUGAAGCUGGCCGGGCCACUCACGUUCAAUGAAAUGAUCCAGCCUGUGUGCCUGCCCAACUCUGAAGAGAACUUCCCCGAUGGAAAAGUGUGCUGGACGUCAGGAUGGGGGGCCACAGAGGAUGGAGCAGGUGACGCCUCCCCUGUCCUGAACCACGCGGCCGUCCCUUUGAUUUCCAACAAGAUCUGCAACCACAGGGACGUGUACGGUGGCAUCAUCUCCCCCUCCAUGCUCUGCGCGGGCUACCUGACGGGUGGCGUGGACAGCUGCCAGGGGGACAGCGGGGGGCCCCUGGUGUGUCAAGAGAGGAGGCUGUGGAAGUUAGUGGGAGCGACCAGCUUUGGCAUCGGCUGCGCAGAGGUGAACAAGCCUGGGGUGUACACCCGUGUCACCUCCUUCCUGGACUGGAUCCACGAGCAGAUGGAGAGAGACCUAAAAACCUGAAGAGGAAGGGGACAAGUAGCCACCUGAGUUCCUGAGGUGAUGAAGACAGCCCGAUCCUCCCCUGGACUCCCGUGUAGGAACCUGCACACGAGCAGACACCCUUGGAGCUCUGAGUUCCGGCACCAGUAGCAGGCCCGAAAGAGGCACCCUUCCAUCUGAUUCCAGCACAACCUUCAAGCUGCUUUUUGUUUUUUGUUUUUUUGAGAUGGAGUCUCGCUCUGUUGCCCAGGCUGGAGUGCAGUGGCGAAAUCCCUGCUCACUGCAGCCUCCGCUUCCCUGGUUCAAGCGAUUCUCUUGCCUCAGCUUCCCCAGUAGCUGGGACCACAGGUGCCCGCCACCACACCCAACUAAUUUUUGUAUUUUUAGUAGAGACAGGGUUUCACCAUGUUGGCCAGGCUGCUCUCAAACCCCUGACCUCAAAUGAUGUGCCUGCUUCAGCCUCCCACAGUGCUGGGAUUACAGGCAUGGGCCACCACGCCUAGCCUCACGCUCCUUUCUGAUCUUCACUAAGAACAAAAGAAGCAGCAACUUGCAAGGGCGGCCUUUCCCACUGGUCCAUCUGGUUUUCUCUCCAGGGGUCUUGCAAAAUUCCUGACGAGAUAAGCAGUUAUGUGACCUCACGUGCAAAGCCACCAACAGCCACUCAGAAAAGACGCACCAGCCCAGAAGUGCAGAACUGCAGUCACUGCACGUUUUCAUCUCUAGGGACCAGAACCAAACCCACCCUUUCUACUUCCAAGACUUAUUUUCACAUGUGGGGAGGUUAAUCUAGGAAUGACUCGUUUAAGGCCUAUUUUCAUGAUUUCUUUGUAGCAUUUGGUGCUUGACGUAUUAUUGUCCUUUGAUUCCAAAUAAUAUGUUUCCUUCCCUCA